AGGAGCCGCCGCCAGUGGAGGGCCGGGCGCUGCGGCCGCGGCCGGGGCGGGCGCAGGGCCGAGCGGACGGGGGGGCGCGGGCCCCCCGGGAGGCCGCGGCCACUCCCCCCCGGGCCGGCGCGGCGGGGGAGGCGGAGGAUGGAAACACCCUUCUACGGCGAUGAGGCGCUGAGCGGCCUGGGCGGCGGCGCCAGUGGCAGCGGCGGCAGCUUCGCGUCCCCGGGCCGCUUGUUCCCCGGGGCGCCCCCGACGGCCGCGGCCGGCAGCAUGAUGAAGAAGGACGCGCUGACGCUGAGCCUGAGUGAGCAGGUGGCGGCAGCGCUCAAGCCUGCGGCCGCGCCGCCUCCUACCCCCCUGCGCGCCGACGGCGCCCCCAGCGCGGCACCCCCCGACGGCCUGCUCGCCUCUCCCGACCUGGGGCUGCUGAAGCUGGCCUCCCCCGAGCUCGAGCGCCUCAUCAUCCAGUCCAACGGGCUGGUCACCACCACGCCGACGAGCUCACAGUUCCUCUACCCCAAGGUGGCGGCCAGCGAGGAGCAGGAGUUCGCCGAGGGCUUCGUCAAGGCCCUGGAGGAUUUACACAAGCAGAACCAGCUCGGCGCGGGCGCGGCCGCUGCCGCCGCCGCCGCCGCCGCCGGGGGGCCCUCGGGCACGGCCACGGGCUCCGCGCCCCCCGGCGAGCUGGCCCCGGCGGCGGCCGCGCCCGAAGCGCCUGUCUACGCGAACCUGAGCAGCUACGCGGGCGGCGCCGGGGGCGCGGGGGGCGCCGCGACGGUCGCCUUCGCUGCCGAACCUGUGCCCUUCCCGCCGCCGCCACCCCCAGGCGCGUUGGGGCCGCCGCGCCUGGCUGCGCUCAAGGACGAGCCACAGACGGUGCCCGACGUGCCGAGCUUCGGCGAGAGCCCGCCGUUGUCGCCCAUCGACAUGGACACGCAGGAGCGCAUCAAGGCGGAGCGCAAGCGGCUGCGCAACCGCAUCGCCGCCUCCAAGUGCCGCAAGCGCAAGCUGGAGCGCAUCUCGCGCCUGGAAGAGAAAGUGAAGACCCUCAAGAGUCAGAACACGGAGCUGGCGUCCACGGCGAGCCUGCUGCGCGAGCAGGUGGCGCAGCUCAAGCAGAAAGUCCUCAGCCACGUCAACAGCGGCUGCCAGCUGCUGCCCCAGCACCAGGUGCCCGCGUACUGAGUCCGCGCGCGGGGCGCAUGCGCGGCCACCCUCCCCAAGGGGCGGGCUCGCGGGGGGGUGUCGUGGGCGCCCCGGACUUGGAGAGGGUGCGGCCCUGGGGACCCCCCCUCCCCGAGUGUGCCCAGGAACUCAGAGAGGGCGCGGCCCCCGGGGAUUCCCCCCCCCCGAGGGUGCCCAGGACUCGACAAGCUGGACCCCCUGCUCCCGGGGGGGCGAGCGCAUGACCCCCCCGCCCUCGCGCUGCCUCUUUCCCCCGCGCGGCCGCCCCGUGUUGCACAAACCCGCGCGUCUCGGCUGCCCCUUUGUACACCGCGCCGCGGAAGGGGGCUCCGAGGGGGCGCAGCCUCAAACCCUGCCUUUCCUUUACUUUUACUUUUUUUUUUUUUUCUUUGGAAGAGAGAAGAACAGAGUGUUCGAUUCUGCCCUAUUUAUGUUUCUACUCGGGAACAAACGUUGGUUGUGUGUGUGUGUGUUUUCUUGUGUUGGUUUUUUAAAGAAAUGGGAAGAAGAAAAAAAAAUUCUCCGCCCCUUUCCUCGAUCUCGCUCCCCCCUUCGGUUCUUUCGACCGGUCCCCCCUCCCUUUUUUGUUCUGUUUUGUUUUGUUUUGCUACGAGUCCACAUUCCUGUUUGUAAUCCUUGGUUCGCCCGGUUUUCUGUUUUCAGUAAAGUCUCGUUACGCCAGCUCGGCUCUCCGCCUCCUUCUUCCCCCGCCGGGGCCUGGCGGGCUGGGCGGGGCCUGGUUCGCUU